GAACUUGGGGGACCCAGCGAAAUGGAAGAAGUUAGGUGUCCAGAGCACGGGACUUUCUGCUUUCUUAAGACCGGCGUCCGCGAUGGCCCGAAUAAAGGAAAGAGCUUCUACGUGUGCCGGGCAGACACGUGCAGCUUCGUGCGGGCCACCGACAUUCCUGUUUCCCAUUGCUUAUUGCAUGAGGACUUUGUGGUAGAGCUUCAGGGUUUGCUUCUGCCACAGGACAAGAAAGAAUACAGAUUGUUCUUCCGAUGCAUUAGAAGUAAGGCAGAGGGGAAACGCUGGUGUGGAAGUAUUCCAUGGCAGGAUCCUGAUUCCAAAGAACAUUCUGUAUCCAAUAAGUCUCAGCAUGCAUCUGAGACAUUUCAUCAUUCUUCCAACUGGCUGAGAAAUCCAUUCAAGGUACUUGACAAGAAUCAAGAACCAGCUCUCUGGAAACAGCUCAUCAAAGGUGAAGGUGAGGAAAAGAAGGCUGAUAAGAAGCAAAGAGAAAAGGGAGAUCAGCUUUUCGAUCAAAAGAAAGAACAGAAGCCUGAAAUGAUGGAGAAAGACCUCUCAUCUGGCCUGGUACCAAAGAAAAAACAAUCUGUAGUUCAAGAGAAGAAGCAAGAAGAGGGAGCAGAGAUUCAGUGUGAGGCAGAGACUGGAGGCACACACAAAAGAGACUUUUCUGAAAUUAAAUCUCAACAGUGCCAAGGUAAUGAGCUUACAAGACCAUCUGCAUCUUCUCAGGAGAAAUCAAGUGGUAAGAGUCAAGAUGUCCAAAGAGAAUCAGAACCUCUGAGAGAAAAGGUUACCCAGCUUUUGCCUCAAAAUGUUCACAGUCACAACUCAAUAAGCAAGCCCCAGAAAGGGGGACCCCUCAACAAGGAGUACACGAACUGGGAGGCUAAAGAAACAAAGGCAAAGGAUGGCCCUAGCAUACAGGCCACCCAGAAAAGCCUGCCUCAGGGGCAUUUCCAAGAGCGGCCGGAGACCCACAGUGUGCCUGCUCCUGGAGGACCAGCGGCUCAGGCUGCACCAGCAGCACCAGGGCUUUCCCUGGGUGAGGGCCGUGAAGCUGCCACAAGCAGUGACGACGAGGAGGAAGAUGAUGUUGUUUUUGUUUCCUCUAAGCCUGGGAGCCCCCUACUCUUUGACUCGACUCUGGACUUAGAGACGAAGGAAAACCUCCAAUUCCCUGAUCGAAGUGUGCAAAGAAAGGUGUCUCCUGCCUCAGGUGUUUCCAAGAAGGUAGAACCCUCAGACCCAGUAGCCCGGCGUGUCUACCUUACAACACAACUGAAACAAAAGAAGAGCACACUGGCAUCAGUGAACAUCCAGGCUCUUCCAGACAAGGGUCAGAAGUUGAUCAAACAAAUCCAGGAGCUGGAGGAAGUACUCAGUGGUCUUACCCUUUCCCCAGAGCAAGGAACUAAUGAGAAGAGUAACAGUCAAGUACCACAGCAGAGUCACUUCACCAAAACUACCACUGGCCCUCCCCACCUGGUGCCUCCCCAACCCCUUCCUCGUCGUGGUACCCAACCUGUGGGUUCUCUAGAACUAAAGUCUGCCUGCCAGGUGACUGCUGGAGGAUCCAGUCAGUGCUAUCGAGGUAACACCUAUUUGUAUGCAGGCCAUACAAACCAAGAUCACGUUCAUGCAGUGUGGAAAAUCACAAGUGAAGCCAUCGGUCAACUGCAUCGCUCACUUGAGUCAUGUCCUGGUGAGACGGUUGUGGCAGAAGAUCCCGCCGGGCUGAAGGUCCCUUUGCUACUACACCAGAAGCAGGCAUUGGCUUGGUUACUAUGGCGAGAAAGUCAGAAGCCACAAGGAGGAAUUCUGGAUGAUAUGGGCUUAGGAAAAACCCUGACAAUGAUUGCGCUCAUCCUGACCCAGAAGAAUCAAGAGAAAAAGGAAGAAAAGGAGAAAAGCACAGCUUUGACGUGGCUCUCCAAAGAUGACUCUUGUGACUUUACUUCCCAUGGAACACUAAUCAUCUGUCCUGCCUCCCUGAUCCAUCAUUGGAAAAAUGAGGUGGAGAAACGGGUGAACAGCAACAAACUAAGAGUCUAUCUCUACCAUGGGCCAAACCGGGAUUCACGUGCCAGAGUCCUCUCUACAUAUGACAUCGUGAUCACUACCUAUAGCCUCGUGGCCAAGGAGAUUCCCACAAACAAGCAAGAGGCAGAGAUCCCAGGUGCAAACCUCAAUGUGGAGACGUUGAGUAUCCACUAUGGGUCAGGUGCUGUUUCGUCAAGAGCAGCCAGAUUCCCACUUCAGGGCACCUCAACACCUUUGCUUCGAAUAGCCUGGGCUCGAAUCAUAUUGGAUGAAGCUCACAAUGUUAAGAAUCCCCGAGUGCAGACUUCCAUAGCUGUGUGUAAGCUACAAGCCUGUGCCCGUUGGGCUGUCACUGGAACCCCCAUUCAAAACAACUUAUUGGAUAUGUAUUCGCUGCUGAAGUUUCUCCGUUGCUCUCCAUUUGAUGAGUUCAAUCUGUGGAGGAGUCAGGUUGACAAUGGCUCAAAGAAAGGAGGAGAACGGUUAAGUAUUUUAACCAAGAGCCUUUUGCUGAGGAGAACAAAAGACCAGCUGGACUCUACUGGCAGACCUUUGGUGAUACUGCCCCAGCGUAAAUUUCAGUUGCACCAUUUAAAGCUUUCUGAAGAUGAAGAGACUGUUUACAAUGUGUUUUUUGCAAGAUCAAGGUCAGCUCUGCAAUCCUAUCUAAAAAGACAUGAAAGUAGAGGCAACCAAUCUGGAAGAAGCCCUAAUAAUCCAUUCAGUAGAGUGGCACUGGAGUUUGGGUCUGAGGAGCCUAGACACUCGGAGGCAGCAGACUCACCGAGAUCCAGCACCGUCCACAUACUGUCCCAGUUGCUGAGACUCCGCCAGUGUUGCUGUCAUCUUUCUUUACUGAAGUCGGCCCUGGAUCCAAUGGAACUGAAGGGUGAAGGUCUUGUCCUUUCCCUGGAAGAACAGCUCAGUGCUUUGACCUUGUCAGAACUCCGUGACUCAGAGCCAUCUUCCACUGUUUCCCUUAACGGCACCUUCUUCAAGAUGGAGCUUUUUGAAGGCAUGCGAGAGAGCACCAAGAUUUCAUCUCUGUUGGCAGAAUUGGAGGCAAUUCAAAGAAAUUCAGCAUCCCAAAAGAGUGUCAUUGUCUCUCAGUGGACCAACAUGCUGAAAGUUGUAGCAUUGCACCUGAAGAAGCAUGGACUGACUUAUGCCACCAUCGAUGGCUCUGUCAAUCCCAAGCAGAGAAUGGACUUGGUAGAGGCAUUUAACCACUCCAGAGGCCCUCAGGUAAUGCUAAUCUCUCUCUUGGCCGGAGGUGUUGGUCUAAACCUGACUGGAGGAAAUCACCUCUUUCUUUUGGACAUGCACUGGAAUCCAUCACUUGAAGAUCAAGCUUGUGACCGAAUUUACCGAGUAGGGCAGCAGAAAGAUGUUGUCAUACACAGAUUUGUUUGUGAGGGAACAGUAGAAGAAAAGAUCUUACAGCUCCAAGAAAAAAAGAAAGAUUUGGCCAAACAAGUUCUAUCAGGGUCUGGAGAAUCUGUCACCAAGCUCACCUUGGCUGACCUCAGAGUCCUUUUUGGCAUCUAACCUCCUGUGGAUAAGGGCUCAGAAUAGCACCAUUGCUGGUUUGUAUUAGGAUCUGGGAAUAACAACCUAACCAUGAGCCUUGAACUCUGUUCUUUGCAUUUCAAUUUCACCGUCAAGCCUUUCACCUUCCUCAAAAUGAGGCAUAAUCUUAUCCCCAGAAUUGAGGAGGGGUUGUGUUAACCAAUUAGUUAACCAAUUAUGUUAAUAAUUUAUUUAAUGAGUGGUAUGGAAACCAAUUGAUUUUUUUAGAUAAAAGAAUAUGUUUUAGAGUUGGAUGAUUUUGGAAAACAACUCUGGCAGAAUUGUAUAUAAGCUUCAGUAAAGUUCAAAAAGCGGGCCAGGUGUGGUGGCUCAUGCCUGUAAUCCCGACACUUUGGGAGGCCAAGGCAGGAGGAUGGCUUGAAGCCAGUAGUUCAAGACCAGCCUGGGCAACAUAGUAAGACCCCAUCUCUAUGAAGAAUAAAAAAAUGAGCUAGGCGUGGUAGUGCACACCUGUAGUCCUAGCUACUUGGGAGGCUGAGGCAGGAGGAUCCCUUGAGUCCAGGAGGUUGAGGCUGCAGUGAGCUGUGAUUGUGCCACUGUUUUCCAGCCUGGGCAAUACAGUGAGACCCUGUCUCAAAAAAAGGAAAAAAAAGCUCAAAAAGUUCUGUGUUGCCUUUCUCUUCUUAGCUGAUGAUGGGAGAACCAGUUACUACCUUCUCUAACACAGGCUCCAUCCUAUCUCUUCAUCUCUUCUUGCCAGUGAUGUUGCACCUGUAACCAUCUUUUUAUGGGUGGAGCAGAGAGUCAAUCCCUGCAGCCACCCUGCAGCCAGCCAUCUCUGCAGUUCUCUCAGUGCAGGCAGUUCUUCCUCUCAGGCUGAAGAUCAAGGAGAUGCUUUGUACAUGAACAGAUGCUGAGUAUCUGUUAUCAUUGUAUUGUUUAGUGUCAGUGUAUCAUUUAGUAUUUGUAUCACUGUACCAUUUAGUGUUGUAUAUCACUCAGUCAUUUAAUAUUGGUUAUCACCAUACAGUUUAAUAUUUGUAUCAUUUGGUUCAUUGUAUCGUUUAGUAUUUCUAUUAUAACAUUUCUAUUUGUAGUAUUUGUAUAAUAUUUGUGUCAUUUUUAAUAGUAUUUGUAUUUUUACAAAUUUGCAGUAUUUGUAGCAUUUAGUAUCAUUGUUUCAUUUAGUAUUUGGUACAAUCUAAUAAAUACUAAUCCAGUCCAAUACUAAUCCAAUCCAAUACUAAUAAUACUAUUGGUACAAUCCAAUACUAAUAAUACUAUUGGUACAAUCCAAUACUAAUAAUACUAACAGUAGUAUUGAUACAAUCUAAUAAAUAAUGUGUUUGACAGUGUAGCAGAAAUAAUGCUAUGUGUUCACCAAACCCACUUCCUUUUCCUCCCGGGCACCCAGAGAGACUGUAUUUCCCAGUUUUUGCUGCAGUUUGACGGGGUCCAUAUCAAUGGACUGUGGAGAGAAGCGAUUGAUGUAAGUCACUUCUAGGUGGCCCUCUACCACUUUCCAAAAGAUCAUUCAUGCUGUUUCUUCCCUCCUCAGCCUAUGGGAUGCAAAGGAACUGAUGGAAGAUUACAAGGCCCUAGGGAAGGUGAAGCCACUAGCUCAGCAGUUCUUAGCCUAGUUUUUGGCCAUCAGCCCUUCUAUUAGACUAGUGAAGCCUCAGUCCCAGGAUGGCUCCCCAUGUACACUUCCCUCCUCGCCCCAGCUCACCUACACUGGACUAUGACAUGAUCAAGGAAUCUUUUUUUUUAAGCUACUGAGAUUUCUGUGUUGUUUACAUAGCAGUUUGUACCCUAAACAAACACUUGAGAUUUUAUACUUCAGGAAACUAUUCAGAUUUCCUUCUCAUUAGCAAUUGUUCCAAAAACACUUACUCUGCUAAUUUCUGCUAGAAAGAAUCACAGUUCUUCUAACACAGAAACAUUUCUGUCCCUUGAGUUGGGAAACAAGACCCUAUGUUAACCCAGUCAGAGUGUGGACUGAGGCAUUCGGAGCCUAUUUAAGCAGAAGUUUUCUAUAAGGACAAGAUUUAAAGGCUUACAAAGGUAAAGACAAUGGCCUGGUGGGAAGAAUUCUAGUCUAGAACGUUUGAGAUUUGACUCUAGUUCUAGGUUCAUCUUAGCUGGGUGUGUAACGUUGAAAAAAUUGGCCGGGUGCAGUGGCUCAGGCCUGUCAUCCCAGCACUUUGGGAGGCCGAGGCAGACGGAUCACGAGGUCAAGAGAUCAAGACCAUCUUGGCCAACAUGGUGAAACCCCGUCUCUACUAAAAAUACAAAAAUUAGCUGAGCGUGGUGGCGUGCGCCUGUAGUCCCAGCUACUGGGGAGGAUAAGGCAGGAGAAUCGCUUGAACCUGGGAGGUGGAGGUUGCAGUGAGCUGAGAUCGCGCCAUUGCACUCCAGCCUGGUGACAGAGCGAGACUCCGUCUCAAAAAAAAAAAAAAAAAAAAAGAGAGAGAAAAAAAUCCUUACUUUCUCUACACUCUGAUUUCCUCAUUUGUAAGGUGGGCAGUUUUCAGAACUUAGCAGCAAUAAGGUUUCUGAUAAAAUCAAGAAGCAAAGGAAGUAACAUUGCCUUUUUGAAGUUUUGCUAUAAGAUUGACAUACCAAGGUAAAGAUUGAGUCACCUGAGAAGCAGUGGCUCCCAGGCCAGCAAGAAUGUACAAACCUGGCUCUGCCAUUUGCUGAUUGAUAUUAGGCAAGUUGCAGAUUCCUUGGACAUCUCAAUCCUUUCAUCUGUAAAAUGUGUGGAUUAGCAUGUAUCUCAUGCUCCACUGGGAAUUUCAUAGCAAAUAUAUAUACUACAACAUGGUUGACCAGAUAGAUCAGUAAUGUCAACUAGAAGGUAUUAGAUGAACAUUGUCAGUCUCCAAUCAAGCAUUGUUUAGGGGAGAGGAAUUCUUUCAGGUUCAAGCAUUCUGGCUUUUAGUUUGGAGAGGGAUGCAGGGAUUGUAACUUAAAAUCUUCAGAUAUUGAGGCCAUUGACAAGUAAUCUACUGUAAGGUAGAUGCCUCCUGGUAUUUUAAAACAGCUUUUCUAAUUUCUCAUGUUAUUGUACAUAAGCAAAGCAACCUAGUUAUGUCUUGGGUAGGUGUUCUUAUAGCCGUGAGAUGCUACUGACUUGAGGUGGAUGCAGAAAAAAAUGGAACCACUGCCUUAAUGGGAUGGAAUAUACUAAACAUGCAUUCUUAAAUCCUAGUGCUGGGAUGGAUUACAUGAAUUACAUUGUGGAGCUGCAUAUGUGUCUCCCCUCUUCCCUCCCUGGGGGUUAGGCUGGGUUUGUUUGGUUUUUUUUGUUUUGUCCUCAUGAGGCUUAGCAUCUAAGGGAGACAGGCAUGAAUUAACAGAAGUGGCAUUCUGGUAUCUGUCUCAGCCUCAUAUUCAUUUUAGUGUAAAUCAGUUUCGUCAAGUCUAGGUAUGACAAGGUGGGUCUUUGCACCUUCUAGCGAUGGGCAGCAUCCCACAACACAGUGGUCUAAUUGAGGUGCUGCACUAUGAGUCCUGCCUGUGUUAACCAGCCUUCCUUCAUGUCACAAUACUGCUGCUGGAUUUGCUUUUUACAUCUGCCUAUUGCACCUGACUUGGGCAUGGAUGAUAUGAGGUAAUAAAUGCUUUGAAAACCAUGAAGGGCCACACAAGUGCUAGUGUUAUUGCUGUGGGACAAGGUCUGGGAAUAUGAGAACCAGCAGCAGCAUGGGUGCAGCUGAGAACCAGAUGGUGAACAUCUGUCUCCAAAGUGCAACAUUCCUGAGCACCGGAUUUAUAAGGCAUUUCUUACUCGACAGAAUUGACUUCAUGGAAGGUAUGUAGUUUGACUUUGCCUUAGCCAUGUUGAUCAAAUAGGAGUAUUGUGCAUGCCGCAGCUAGACAGAGUCCUGGGCCCUUUAAAAACCUUGUCAGUGACUCCCAUUGCAGGCCCAGCGCAGUGGUUCACACCUGUAAUCCCAGCAUUUGGGAGGCUGAGGCAGGCAGAUCACUUGAGGCCAAGAGUUCGAGACCAGACUGGCCAACAUGGCAAAACCUCCUCUCUACUAAAAAUACAAAAGUUAGCCAGGCGUGAUGUUGGGUGCCUGUAAUUGCAGCUACUCGGGAGGCUGAGGCAGGAGAAUCACUUGAAUCCAGGAGGCGGAGGUUACAGUGAGCUGAGAUCAUACCACUGCACUCCAGCCUGGGCCACAGAGAAAGAACGGUGAUUCUUUCUAGCAGAAAUUAGCAGAGUAAGUGUUUUUGGAACAAUUGCUAAUGAAAAGAAGGAAAAACAGAAAAAAAAAAUUUUCUGUUUAUGGGAGGUGACUUAUUUCUCUAUCAAUCCUGUGAGUGAUUUAGCAUGGCAAUUCAUGAACACUGAGUUGUUUCCUUGCUCUGAUUGUCUGUUGCUCAAUGAAAUGGCUUUUAGCAGGGCUCAAAGGUGAAGCCAGAUUCUCCUGCACUAAUAGGAUAAGCAUGGAGACACCAGUGUUCAGUGUGGCCUCUGGUUGUCUGAAAUUUUGCUGUCAACUCUAAUACCUUGAAAGAAUUAGGUUUCCAAAGUGGGAUAUUGUGCUGCUGUUUGUGAUAUAGCAUCUAGACUUAGGAAAGGGCAGGAACAAUUUAAAAGCACAUCUGUAGGCACAAAGAGAAUUAUAAUAGAAAUUCAGAAUUCCUAGGCAUAUGACCUAGACUAAAAUGUCUUCAUAACUACAAAUGAAAUCAGGGUCAUUUAUAGUACAAACUACCACAGAAGUCAGUAGUUAGGGGAUGGAGAUAGAUAUGAAAAAAAAAAAAAGCAAACCCAGCCUAACUCCCAGGGAGGGAAGAGGGGCGACAGAUAUGCAGCUACACAAUGUUUUUACUAUCUUGAGUUCUUUUUACCCAGAUUCCAUAGCUAAAUCCAGAUGUAUUAAUAGGUAGAGACUACUUCAGAAAGGAUGAGACUAUUUUCUUGCUUAAUUAUCCACACAGUAAUUCAGAAAUGUAUAUUGAACACUUUUUAUAUGCCAGGCACUGCUGGGCACUGGAAAUAUAAAAGUAAGCAAAAAUGAAAAACUAUCCUGUCCUCCUGAGGCUUAGCAUCUAAGGGAGACAGGCAUUAGUCAACCCCGUGUGGCUGUGAAUCAGCCAUGAUGCUGAGUGCUACAAGAGAGGACUGUGCGGCUGGGAGGGCUUAUAACAGGAUUUGACCUAGUUAGGGAAGAUCUGAGGAAGUGAUGAAAGAAUGGAAAUCAAUAUGUAAGAGCUCACAAGUCAGAGUGAGAUGUUUCUUCCUAUACUGCCUGCUUCUAAUGAGCAUCCACUUCAUUGAACCACCUCUUCAUUGAGCCAAACCUACCAUACAGGGAUACAUUCUCUGGAGGAAAGUUGAGCAACUAUUGCAUUUGGGACAUUAGAGUAUGGGUGGGCUGACAGGUAUGUGUAUGUUUAUUAUCCAAGACAGCCAAGGUGUUUAUCCUGUUACAACAUCCCAGAGGACAGAGGCUCUUAUUUGUGACUCUUUUUUCUUACCUGUAACACCAGAGGCAUAACGUACAUCAUAAUGCUGCAUCUUGUUGACGCUUCAAUGCUCACAAUUCAAAGGUGAUUUCUGAAGCACUUUGUUACACUGGGGACAGCUCCUAAAUCCUCCCACUCUUUUUUUGCCUCACCUUGGAGUCUUGGGCUCUGUUGAUCACUGACUCUGCCAGGUCUUUCAGCAGGCAAGACAGCUCAGUUAAAUUGAGUUUGGACUCCACUGUAGUGCAUGCAUGAGACAGCACCCCCAAUCCCCAACACCCACACACAAACUUUAAAUAUUUGUAACAGAAUUGUUACCAUUAAUAUUGCUUAAAGGCUAACACAUUAGCCAGAACCUAGAUGUCUUCUGGAAAUUUUUUAUUGCAAUGUUACUUCAUCUACAUAAAGUUGUCCAAUCACUGAAACCUCCAACUGAAAUAAAUGGUAAGCUUUUUGUUCUCAA